UCCCUCCUCCUGAAUUCAUAUAGCACUUAAAAAAAUGCUUUUGUGGCACAUAGCACUUUAUACUUUGCAGUAUUUUAAUACAUACUGCAUAGUAAGCAUCUCGAAGUCAAGGUGCUUGUUUCAUAUCCUGUUGCAUUCCUCGCGGUAGCUUGCUGAGGGCCUUGCACAUGGAGCCAUAAGGAAAAUGGAUGGAUGGAUGGAUGGAUGUGUGGGUGGGUGGAUGGAUGGAUGGGUGGACAGUUGGACAGAUGGAUGGAUGGACGGACGGACGGAUGGACCGAUGGACAGAUGGAUAUAUGCUAUUCCUGCUCUGACUCAGUUUUUACUGUAAACAACUGUAUCCAGAAUUAAAAUGUUAAGGAAAUUUUGUAAUUAUUAUGACACCUUUCCUCUUUAUAGAAAUGUACUGUACAUUUGGAAUAUGUAGAAAAUGGGGAAAGCAAUCAAAAAGAAAAAAUUCAGAUUUCUCCACUCAGAGAUGACACUGCUAACAGGCUGAAGCAUGUGUUCCCCUCUUUCUCAUUUGAGUCAUCCCAGGAUGAGGUUAUAUAGAACAUAUGGUUUUCUAACUUGACUUUUUACCUAAUAUCUUAAUACAUGUCUAUACCUAUAAUAUGGAUUUCGUUUCUUUAUCAUUGAGCAUUAGUAUCCUUUUUUUUUUUGCUAUUAAAAGUGAUGUUGUGAAGAACAUUCUUGCACAUAAAUCUUUCCAUACCUCUGAAAUUAUUCCCUUACUAUAAUUUCUAAGAAGUGGAAUUUUGGAAUCAAGAGUAUAAAAAUUUUCAAGCGUUUGAUAUAUAUUGCCAAAUUGCCCUUCAGGAAGGUUGUACCAAUUUACUCUCCCACCAGCUAGCUGCUAAAAUCCUCAUAAAACUGCUGGCAUGACUUCUCAAGGCAACUAGAUAACUAUGUUUGUUGGUGUUAUUGAUUUCAACUUUGUGCUAAAAAUACUUUUAUAUCUGGAAGGAAGGAAUAGGGAUAGAGUACUUUUGUGGCAUCAAUUCCUAAAACCGUGGGAAGCGACUUAAGUGUUCAGGAGAGAAAACGUUUAGAAGCCACUGAUAUAAUGGCUAAGCCCUGAAUUUACAGUGAGGACUAGAUCCUCGAUUUUAUUUUUCUCAGUGAUCUUAUGUUGCACAUGUGCGCACGCACACACACACACACACACAAUGGAAACAACCUUUAAUCUCAGAAUUACAUUUUGUGAUUUAAUUGUUUUUAAAUUUUUAAGUCCUUUGAACUUCUUAGAGAAAGAAAAUAUACAAAGAUUAAACUUCUGUUUUUUUUCUCCUUAGUCUUCAAAUUAAGUGUAAUUUCAGGCACUCAAUUUAAGUAAGUUGCUUAUAGCUCUAAAAGUUCCUGAUUCCCUCUUUAGUGAUUUCAUUCGAUUACUCAUUCAGACCUUUUUCUUUUUAGCUAGAUUGAAUGUGUCCUUUGAACUGUUUCAUUAUCUUGGUAAAACAGCAUUUAUAGAUAGAGUCCAAACUCAGCUUCAUUCUCUGCAGCAAGAUAGACCACACUGUCAUUUUCUUCUGUCACUUUCAGUUUACUUGACAGAGAAAGCUGAAGCAGAAGAGCUUAAAUUAGUUAUAAAUCACAAAAACACUUCUUAAGAUUGGGGUUCCACCAGAGCUUCUUUAAGUGAUUCCUUCUCAUGAAAGUUGAAGCAGACUAAGAAAGUGGGAGUGGAGAGGUGAAUGUUGAUUGAAUAGCCACAGUAUUUUGACAUCGUGUGGAAUGUGUACCCAGGCCUUUUCAAACUUUUUUUCUGGUUAGAAACUAUGCUAAUAAUGGAUGCCAUGGCCUUUAUAAAUAUGUUGGGUUUUGUAAGAAGCAGUAACCAGGAACAUAUUUACAUGAGGACUGGAAACAGAAAAAAAAGGUGAUUCUGAAUUGCUGUGAGGGCAGAACACCCAAGGAGACAAUAGAAAAUUUGUUGCACAGAAUGACUGAAGAGAAGACGCUGACUGCUGAGGGUUUGGUAAAACUCCUCCAGGCUGUGAAGACGACUUUCCCAAACCUGGGCCUUCUGCUAGAGAAGUUGCAGAAAUCAGCCACUUUGCCAAGCACCACAGUCCAACCAAGCCCUGAUGAUUAUGGGACUGAGCUAUUGAGACGCUAUCAUGAAAACCUCUCUGAGAUUUUCACAGACAACCAGAUUUUAUUAAAGAUGAUCUCACACAUGACAAGUUUAGCCCCUGGAGAAAGAGAGGUCAUGGAGAAGCUUGUGAAACGUGACUCUGGUUCAGGUGGUUUCAAUUCUCUGAUAUCAGCAGUUCUAGAAAAGCAGACUCUCUCUGCCACAGCCAUUUGGCAACUGCUGCUGGUGGUUCAGGAGACAAAGACCUGUCCAUUGGACCUGCUCAUGGAGGAAAUACGAAGGGAGCCUGGUGCCGAUGCUUUCUUCCGGGCAGUGACCACCCCAGAACAUGCCACUUUAGAAACAAUCCUGAGGCAUAACCAGUUGAUCUUGGAGGCCAUCCAACAGAAGAUUGAGUACAAGCUCUUUACCUCGGAGGAGGAGCACCUGGCAGAGACUGUGAAAGAGAUUCUGAGCAUUCCCUCUGAGACAGCCAGCCCUGAAGCUUCCCUGAGAGCAGUGCUGAGCAGAGCCAUGGAAAAAUCAGUCCCGGCCAUUGAAAUAUGCCACCUCCUGUGCAGUGUCCACAAAUCUUUUCCAGGCCUGCAGCCUGUCAUGCAGGAGUUGGCAUACAUUGGUGUCCUUACUAAGGAAGAUGGAGAGAAGGAAACGUGGAAGGUGAGUAAUAAAUUUCACCUUGAAGCCAACAACAAAGAAGAUGAAAAGGCAGCCAAAGAAGACAGCCAGCCUGGGGAACAGAAUGAUCAAGGAGAGACUGGUUCCUUGCCAGGACAGCAAGAGAAAGAGGCUUCAGCCUCCCCAGACCCUGCCAAGAAGAGCUUCAUCUGUAAGGCCUGCGACAAAAGCUUCCAUUUCUACUGCCGCCUAAAGGUGCACAUGAAGCGCUGCCGGGUGGCUAAGAGCAAACAGGUGCAGUGUAAGGAGUGCAGUGAGACCAAGGAUUCAAAGAAAGAGCUGGACAAACAUCAGCUGGAGGCCCAUGGUGCAGGUGGAGAGCCCGAUGCCCCCAAGAAGAAGAAGAAGAGGCUUCCAGUGACAUGUGACCUCUGUGGCAGAGAAUUUGCCCAUGCCUCAGGCAUGCAGUACCAUAAGCUGACAGAGCACUUCGAUGAGAAGCCUUUCUCCUGUGAAGAGUGUGGGGCGAAGUUUGCAGCCAAUUCCACCCUGAAGAACCACCUUCGCCUUCACACCGGGGACCGCCCGUUCAUGUGCAAGCACUGCCUCAUGACCUUCACCCAGGCCUCCGCCCUGGCCUAUCACACCAAGAAGAAGCACUCAGAAGGGAAAAUGUAUGCAUGCCAGUACUGUGAUGCUGUGUUUGCCCAGUCUAUUGAGCUGUCCCGCCACGUGAGGACCCACACCGGGGACAAGCCCUAUGUCUGCAGAGACUGUGGCAAGGGCUUCCGGCAAGCCAAUGGCCUCUCCAUCCAUCUGCACACCUUUCACAACAUAGAAGAUCCUUAUGACUGCAAGAAGUGCAGGAUGAGUUUCCCCACUCUUCAGGAUCACCGGAAGCACAUCCAUGAGGUGCACUCCAAAGAGUACCACCCCUGCCCCACGUGUGGGAAGAUCUUCAGUGCCCCGUCCAUGCUGGAGCGGCACGUGGUGACCCACGUUGGAGGGAAGCCCUUCAGCUGCGGGAUCUGCAACAAGGCCUACCAGCAAUUGUCUGGUUUGUGGUACCACAAUCGAACCCACCACCCUGACGUAUUUGCUGCUCAGAACCACCGAUCUUCCAAGUUCUCAUCACUCCAGUGCAGCUCCUGUGACAAAACCUUCCCCAACACCAUUGAGCACAAGAAGCACAUCAAAGCAGAACAUGCAGAUAUGAAGUUCCAUGAAUGUGACCAGUGUAAGGAGCUCUUCCCCACGCCAGCCUUGCUGCAGGUUCAUGUCAAGUGCCAGCAUUCAGGGUCCCAGCCAUUCCGGUGCUUGUACUGUGCUGCUACUUUCCGUUUUCCUGGAGCAUUGCAGCACCAUGUCACCACGGAGCACUUCAAGCAGUCAGAGACCACCUUCCCCUGUGAGCUCUGUGGGGAACUCUUCACCUCCCAGGCCCAGCUUGACAGUCACCUGGAAUCUGAGCACCCAAAGGUGAUGAGCACGGAAACCCAGGCCGCAGCCUCACAGAUGGCGCAGGUGAUCCAAACCCCAGAGCCGGUGGCCCCGACAGAGCAGGUGAUCACUUUGGAGGAGACCCAGCUUGCCGGGUCGCAGGUGUUUGUGACGUUGCCAGAUUCUCAGGCAUCUCAGGCCAGCUCUGAGCUCGUGGCGGUGACUGUGGAGGACUUGCUGGAUGGCACAGUGACGCUGAUCUGUGGUGAGGCCAAAUGAGCAGCCUUUCAUCCGGCAGAGCCUUCCUGCGUUUGCAGCAGAGAGGAGGCCCCACAGCUUGCCCUUUGCCCUCCAUCCCUGGCUGUCCUGAGUGGUGAGCAUCUUAGCUUAGCACCAACCAACACAGUCUCACCUAGAAAACAGAUGGAAGCUUCGUUGUUCUCAUAGAACCAACAGCAUCUGAGCCCUCAACACCAACAGCACCAUCCUCUGUAGCAGACAGGCCUCCCUCCCCACAGGCCCGCUGCUGCGGCCUCUAUGACACUGUCCAUCCCCAAGUGACAUGUGGCUUCAGAAGUAGAGUCUGAAAGAGCAGUGGGAUGGGAGCUGGUGACCAGGGUACCCCAGGAGGCAUGAUGUGCCGACAGCGCUCAGUGGGCAGAAUGGCAGUUAGAUAUGGGACUUGGCCCACAGUGGGGGCUGCAAAUGCUGCCACUGCCUCUGGCCAUUUAAAGUGAGAGGGGCACCAACAGACAAUUCGGGGACCUUAGGCCCCUUCCUGAGGCACACUUGGCCCCUUCCUCGGUCCUAUCAUCCUACCCUCUGCUGGGGUUCCCCCUCCACCCAGUGGCCACGCCCAGCACCCUAUUGAUGGCUAUAGGACAGGUAGCCCUCAUUUCCAUGCCUGAUAACCCCUUGUCAGUUGUCAGCUCUUCCCAAAACAAAGCUCUGGAGUUUCUGCUGGAAGUGUUUAAUGUGAGGCAUCAGCUGCUAGACAGUGUCUGCCUUUCCAGGACAUUCUUCUUGGUAUUCCUUACCUGAAGCCUGGUUCCCACAGCUCUUCCGUGUCAUCUUCAUCCCCUUCCUUUAAUCAAAGGCUGAAAUCUCUGCCUGACCUGGCAGCCUGGCUCCCUCUGGGUCAUAUGGUGCAGACUGUGACCAGCACCAGGCAGGCAGUCCUGUCUGCGUGUGGAGGAGCAGCCGUGACUGCCCGUGGCUCUGCUGCCGCCCACUCCCUGCCUUGUGAGUGGCCUGCUGCCUCACCUCCCGCAGGCCGCCACACUUAUUGCAGGUCAGUGAUCCUUUGGAGUUUGAAUUUCACAAAGCUUUUUUUAUCUUCAGUUCCUAAAAUAUAAUCUGAUAAUUAAUGGUUUGUGGAAUCCAUUAUGAAGUGCAAUUAGAUAGAUGUAGGUUCCUGCCGUUUGGAGAGAAUGACUAGCAUUUAUCUUCUUUUCCUUCCAUGCCAAAGGUUGGAGUCUGCUGGUGCGGUGUUUACACACCAGGCAGGGCUGUCUGCCACCUUGUGUGGCUUGACCCCCUGUGGAGGGGAGUGCCUGGUUGGAUCCCACACUGGCAGAGAUGGGGCCACCCCUUCCUUCCAGGCACAUCUCACAUUGCCAUGUACAGAGGCAGGAGUCACGUUUGGUCACCAUGGAAGCUUUUAUUGCUCCCACAUGGUCAGGUCUCACCCUGCUUGAAGCGCAGAAGGCACAGCCUUACUGACCAGCACGCCCACUGACUGGCAUCUGCCGGCUUUGUGCAGGCAGCCCCGACGGUUUCCACAGCGAGCGCCAGCUCCGGCCAGCCUGGGACAGCUCAUCCCAGCCGACUACACCUGCUUCUGGUCCUGUCCACAUUUUGAUACGCAGAUCACUUGAGCUUGUCAAUUAGGGUUCUGCCAUUCUGAAAUAAAUGAAGUUUCUAAAGCAGAGUCGGCCUCAGAAGCCAAAAACUGACCAGAAGAUGGUGCUCAAACCUUUAAGACUUCAUCUCCAUGUGAAGGGCUCACUGUUUCUACCAAGGCUGUGCCUGUAUUAAGGCUUUUCCGUCCUGGGAACUGUCAGUCUGGGAGAGCUCUUGAUCUGCAGGUGGCAAAAUGGCACUGAAUAUCCCCUUGGCAGCAGAGAAAACCCACUGAAAGAUCGUAGAGUGGCACAUGCUUACAGGGCAUUGGUGCCAAGUCCAGUGGAUGAGAAUCCAGCCCCUCACAAGCUGUGGGAUGGGGCUUGGGAGUUGCAGUGAAUGUCAUUAAAAUUUCUUCCAAAACAAAACUAGAAAUAAUUGCUGAGGGCUUAUAGGGAAGUGAUUUAAAAAGAAAAAACAAACAACAACAAAAAAAACUCUUCGGAAUAAAGAGGGCUGUAAAUUUUGAAUUCCAGUGUCAGAUCCUUUCAAGCACUGAGAAAUUCUUUCUCAGGUUUCUUUUUUUGGGGGAGACAGGGUCUUGCUCUGUCACCCAGACUGGAACACAGUGGCACGAUCUUGGCUCACUGCAACCUCUGCGGGCUCACGCAAUCCUCCUGCCACAGCUUCCCAAGUAGCUGGGACCACAGGCGUGAGCCACCACUGCUGGCCAGUUUUUGUAUUUUUUUUUUUUUUUGUAGAGACAGGGUCUCGCCAUGUUGCCCAGGCUGGUUUAAAACUCCUGAGCUCAAGCAGUUCUCCCACCUGGGCCUCCCAAAGUGCUAGGAUUACAGACAUGAGCCACUACGCCUGGCCAGGUUUCUGUUGGAGACCCAGAUUGUGACAAGACAUUUGUUUUCUUCGGAAUCACCAGAUUUGCAGCUUACUGUGCCGAGAGUGGACUGGCUGCCGGGGCCCAUCAGAUGCCCUCUGGCCCAUGGCACACUCAGCAGAAGGCACAAACCCAGUGCUGGUUCUCAUCAAGAAAGAGGGGAAGGCCCUUCCCGAGUUUACUGUCUGCUCUGAGUGGGCUCCGCACUGGCUGACUGAUUUUAUAGUCUUGCUCUCUAGAGAAGCCCAGGCAUGGAUCUUAUAGGAAAACUUUCUGACUCUGCUUGGCCAUUUUAUCCUUUUCUCCUACUUCUGCCCAAGAGACCUGAAUUGCUGCCAUAGAGGACAGUGUUUGUGUGGUCUCCUGAGUCCACAUCGCUCGCUUCCAUGGGGUCCCGGUGUUGUUUUUGCCUCGUUCCCCAUAGGCUGCUGCCCUUAUGGCCUCUGGACUGAACUCUGGGGCCUUUGGGGUGGUGUGAAGGAGUCUGUGGGCUUCUUGGAACACAUGGAUCUGUUCGGUGGGUCCCCAGACCUCUGCUCCCAGAGCUCAUGGCCCAGGUGGUGAGGAGGGAAAGGCAGUCAGAUUCCAGGCUGGAGUGUGAUUCUGUGGGAAUACUGGGGUCAGUUAUGGAACAGGACUUGCCCAUCAUAGGUAAGUGAGACAGCAAAUAGAUGAUUCAAGAGCAAGGAUUACUGCGGGAAGGUGAGACUCCUACUGUCCACGCGCAUGAGCAGAACCUGGAACCAGAGGGGCAGGGACCAGGGGUCUUUACUCAUUUAUUUUAUGGGUAAAGAGACAUGAAGAGACAGCCUCUCUCUUCUGUCUCAGAAGCUCUGUGUUUGGGAAACUUUGAGCCCAGUGAGUAGCAGGGUCUGCAGUGUGAGUACCAGGUUUCCCUGGCAAUCCAGGUCUCCUCUGAGGAAGCAUUCUGACUUCCCACUGACCACGGAAGGCAUGUCAGCUUCAUGCCUCGGGCUAGAGUUCUGAUAAUCGGGGCUGAGGGGUGAAAAGAAAUCCAGUCAGACAGACAGUGGGGAGACAGGUCCCUGCCCUUUAUUUGCGGGAUCAAUCAGGGACUCCCAGAAAGGAAGGAGAAUGGUGAGAAGGGCCCUAAGAGUUCGUCUCUCACCUGGGGGCUGGUGACGUGGUCACCACAAGCUGAAGACAGGCUAAUGGGGUGGCGGGUGUGUGUUUAAACCUCACGUGCCUGGAAGCUGCACAUUGACCAAAGGAGGGAGGGAAGUGCUAACCAUGUAUAGAGUGGGCAGGCGGUUCCAGGGAGACAAGCAGCAUGUUAUUAAAUUGGGCCUAGGCAGUUGGACGAUAAUGGAGAAAAAGCAGGGAUGCUAUAAUGAGUCCUCCCCAAGGGUGAGUUCAGCACCCCAGCCCUGUUCUGCUUGUAUCCCAGUGAUACUUGGGAGGUAGGAAGAAAAUGGGAGUAAGAGAACAAUUUGGGGCUGAAGGGAGUGUCAGAGGCACGUUGAUCCUUGUUUUGUUGUCAUGGAAACUUCGGGGCUGGUGGGACUUAGGCCAAAAGCUCAGAGGCACAGCCAAAAUUUAGAAGCUUGCUACUCCUACGACUCGGCCUAUAAGGAAGAGAGAAGCUGUCUGUACUUUGGGGACUACAUUGCUGAAGGAAAAAAAUCACUCCCUGGCUAAUUAAGAUUGCUUCCAAAUUGGGGGAAUGUGUGUCAUUUCCUUUACCAAGGCCAGUCAUCCCUGCUUCCACCCAUGGUCAGGACAGUCAGCCACUACGUGAUGCUGUAUAAAUUGGAUUACAAACCAUAUUCUUGUUCAGCUUGCACUAAUCUAUAUAAAUAAAAUAUGUACUUUGAAAAAAAUUAGGCUACAUGAGUUUCAAAUGGACUGUGAUGUUAUAGACCUGCUUUCUCUUUGGUUCUGGGCCAGUGUCAGACGGGGACAGGGGUGAUAGGCCUGGUGUCCUAGGGGCCAUUUGUGUACCUUGAGGCCGUGUUAACAUGGCCUGGGGGAAAGAAAGCUCUCCUGUCACUUGGAGUCUCAUUCCUAAACCCUCCUUCCCAGGGAGCAAGUGUGGGGCAGGGUUUCAGAGCACAGGCUUUGGUGUCCAGCCUGGGUACAUCCAGCUGUCCCGCUGUCUAACUGACAUUGUGUGAGAUGCUUACUCUCUCUGAGCUCCCUCCUCCUGGCUCCCAACUUUAUUAUAAAAUGGGGAAAAUGAUUGUGCUUGCCCUACAGAAUUGUAGUAUGAAUUAAAAGUCUGGAUUUAAUGUAUUUAAUAUAGAAAAUUUUAGCUUUUAUUAAUAAAAGUUUUUGGCAUACAA